GCGGAGGGCGGUGCAGCCGGCGAGGGUGACGCAGGGAAGCCGCGGCCGCGUGGGUGCGCGCGUGCUUCGGGGUGGGGCCUCGGGGCGCCGAGCGGGAGAGGGCUCCGGAGGCCGCGGCAGGCCGGUGGCUUAUUUCUGGAAUCGUUUUGCAGAACCUGGGCUUGGUUGUAGUUUAGUCGCAGGGCUGGCUGAGGGUGUUCAUGCAGACACUUCGCUGCACUCCCGACAUUUGCUUAGCUAUUAUUUUUGAGAAAUAGGAAGGACGGCAUGGCGAGUUCCUCUUUGCAGAUACUACUUGCAGAGGGCGCCUUGCGUAACGUGUGGGUUUGGAAAUGAAUCGGAAGAAGACUCAGCAGCAGCCGCAGAAGGAAGCUCUUGAGGAGCUGGGCCCGGUGAAGUAGGAGCCGGGGUAGGCCUCACUCAGGCUGUGCAGAAGGGACACCCAUUCUGGUGCUGGUCACAGAAGCAGGAACCUCAAAGGCCUGUCUACAAACCAUUUAUUCAUUUAUUCAUUGAGGUGCUUUUAGCGAAGUCUCUGCUUCUGGGCGAAUGGUGGCGAGCAAGUAAAAAAGCCUGGGUCUUGUGGCAGAUGACGAACAAGUCAUUCUACAGAAGGCGGCCGUAUGGGCAUAAUAGGGACCGGGCGGCGGGAUCUGUUCUGGGGAGGGAGGAUAGCUGUUCCUGAGGAAAGGACCUUUGAGCUGAGACCUGCAGGAUAAGUCUGGGUGGCACGGAGCAAAGUGGAGGCCAAGAGCCCAGGGGCAGCCCAGUUUCUCCAGCAGGAGGGAACAGGAUGCUUUUUGGAAAUAAAAGUGAGGCACGGUGGCUUGCACCUGAGUCCCAGCUACGCUACUCGGGAGGCCAAGGCAGUAAGAGCGCUUGAGCCCAGGGAGUUCGAGGACAGCCUGGGCCACAGAGUGCGACCUCCGUCUCUAAGAACAAACACAAACAUGGUCAGGAGGCUGUCACUCAGAGACAGGCAGAAUCAAGAGCUGGUCCUGGAGAGACCAGUGGGGCUGUGUAGACUGGGAGCUUUGGUUGUUUGCUGAGAGCAGGAAGCUGCAGGAAGAAGGCAGUGGUCCCCAGCCAGAAUACGGAGUGGCUUGGAGGUGGUCAAAGGUUUGAAGACAGCCACAGUAAAGUGGACAGAGACAAGAAAAAUAGGUACCAAACCGUGCAUCCAGGUAGUCACAGAAAGGAAAUGGGUUUAGAUUGAAGCAAUGUGGGUUAAAGUUAGACCCUGGGGAAACCUUGCAGGGGUCUGUAGGCCUGUGAAGAACUGGACUAGGUGAGAAGAAGAAGCUUUUGACCCAUGUCACUCCCUGGCCCAGAACUAUAUCCUACCCACAGGUGGGUUGAGUUCAGGACUGCUGCUUCCAGCCCCCAGCAGCAAGGUUCAAGUGAGAGCUGACUCACCUAGGGCCCCUUGUUAGAGCCUCAGAGCCAGGUGAAAAGCCACACACAGGCUGGGCGCGAUGGCUCACGCCUGUAAUCCCAGCACUUUGGGAGGCCGAGGCAGGUGGAUCACCUGAGGUCAGGAGUUCAAGACCAUCCUGGCCAACAUGGCAAAAUCCCGUCUCUACUAAAAAUACAAAAAUUAGUCCUGCCUGGUGGCACAUGCCUGUAGUCCCAGCUACUCGGGAGGCUGAGGCAGGAGAAUCGCUUGAACCCGGGAGGCGGAGGUUGCAGUGAGCCGAGAUCAUGCCACUGCACUCCAGCCUGGGUGACAGAGCGGGACUCUGUCUCCAAAAAAAGAAAAGCCACACAGGUGUGUGUGUAGGGGCAAGGGAGUUUCCUACUGUCUUCCUAGCAGAAAAUGGGGAGAAACUGUUAAAGCCAGAAUGAGGGAGGGCUGUGUGUGGCCUGGGACUGGCAACAGAAGUGUCAAGCUGCCAGGUUUCAGGCCAGUACAGAGCACGGUUCUACCUGGGUUAUGUGUUGCCGGCACUAAUGGUUAGAGACAUCUGUCACUGGUGAGGGCAGAAAUGUAUGCAGGAGUGGGUGUGGGAAGCUGGCCUCACUGGUGGGUGGGGUUGGAGACUUUGCCAGGCCUGGUCAGGAAAAGCUGCUACAAAACAGCAAAACUGCUCCUAGUGCAGCGAUCCCCAACCUUUUUGGCAACAGGGAGUAUUUUCCUGGAAGACCAUUUUUCCAUGGAGAGGGAGGGCGGGGCUGGUUUCGGGAUGGAAGUGUUCCAUCUCCCAUCAUCAGGCAUUAGUCAAACUCUCCUAAGGAGCACACAAAACCUACACUCCUGGUGUGCACAGUUCACAGGAGGGCUUCUGCUUCUGUGAGAACCAAAUGUCCCACUGAUGUGACAGGAUCAGAGCGCCAUCGCUGCUCACUUCCUGCAUGCGGCCCUGUUCCUGACAGGCCACGGACCAGUACCUGGGGUUUGGGGUCCCCCGCCCUAGGGGAUGAAAGAAGGGAAACCUGGGUCUAAUGGGUUACUGUGAUUCUCCCUGCGAUGCAGGGAAGAGACAGGACAGAGGUGGGAAGGAACAUGGUCACCAGGAGUCGGGACAGCACUCUUCCAGGUCCUUCCCCUGGGGCUGAGUAAGCACCCUGCGCGUAGCUCUUCCUGGCCGCCUGUGGGCUCUGGGAUCUAAACGGACUAUGCAGCCAUUCUCACUUUCAUUCACAGCUCGGACAGGGACAGUGUGUGUUGAGGCGGAAAGACAAAACAUGUAUGUGAGAGACUUUGUAUGAGCCGGUUCCUGAUGAAGUCCUAUCUUUCAGCCUCGUAUUUACUGCCCAGGCAGAUGGGGCUCUUUUCUUCACCCUCCCGCUUUUUUUUUUUGAGACAGAAAACUUAAUAGAAAUUUUGUUUGCAGUUCUUACAUUCUCAGUGUGAGCCAAUCUGUGACCCACCGCCCCACCCAGAAGUGGCCCAGUCCUGGUGCAGGGUAGGAAGGGAAGGGUGGAGUGAGAAGAGCCCCAUUUUUCCUCAGUGCCAGGGGGCUGGAGACACCACCCCCUUCUCCUGCCUCUGGGCUCCAGGAAGGAGUGCAGAUGGACUCUCAGGCCUAUGGUUCCUCCUCCACACCACUGUCCCCCAGGUUGGAGGGGAGUGAGAGAUACAGGGAGAGAAGGGGACAGAGGCAAGAAAAGGUGUUGAUCAAGAAAGGCAAGAACCAGGGGUGAGGGCUGACAGAGAAUCAAAGAUAAAACACUAGUAGGCCGGGCGCGGUGGCUCAUGCCUGUAAUCCCAGCACUUUCGGAAGCCAAGGCGGGCAGAUCACCUGAGGUCGGGAAUUCGAGACCAGCCUGACCAACAUGGAGAAACCCUGUCUCUACUACAAAUAUAAAAUUAGCCGGGUGUGGUGGCACAUGCCUGUAAUCCCAGCUGCUCAGGAGGCUGAGGCAGGAGAAUCGCUUGAACCUGGGAGGCAGAGAUUGCAGUGAGCCAAGAUCAUGCCACUGCACUCCAGCCUGGGCAACAAGAGCGAAACUCUGUUGGAAAAAAACAAACAGUAAAAAAAAAAAAUUGAGGGAGAGUGGGGGAGGGGAAUAUAACCAAAACCCACCCCAAAUCCAAACCAGCCUCGAAAAAAACGGUGCGGUGCCUGGAAGGGCUUGGAGGCAGGAGGAUGUGGCAGACAGAAGGACAGUGGGGGAGGUAGGGGCUGAGAUGUGGUCUUGGAGCACGGGCAGAUAAGAUCUAGGGGGUAAAGGGAGGAGGAUCUGUGUGUGAUGAGGGCAGACGGGGUUCAGAGAGGAAAACCAAGGCGGGCUGGUGAGUUGUGUGUGUGAAAAGCCUGCGGGCCCUGCACCUGGACAUGACCAGUAAGCCUGGGAAGCUAGGAGCUCGAGAGCAGGCCAAGAAAGGGACUCGGGAGGCAGCAAGGACACGUGUCGGCGUUGCCUGGUGGACACAUUGGUCAUGACGUGCCUGGGCGAAAAGCUGCCAGCAGGGAGUCCCUGAAGAGGAAGGAGAAGGAAUAUGAGCAUGAAAUGGAGCGGCUGGCACGUGAGAAGAUUGCCACGCAGCAGCGGCUGGCAGAGCUCAAGCACGAGCUGAGCCAGUGGAUGGACGUACUGGAGAUUGACCGCGUGCUGCGGCAGACGGGCCAGCCCGAGGAUGACCAGGCCUCCACCUCCACCGCCUCUGAGGGUGAGGACAACAUAGACGAGGAUAUGGAGGAGGACCGGGCGGGCCUGGGCCCACCUAAGCUGAGCCAUCGUCCCCAGCCGGAGCUGCUGAAGUCCACCCUGCCACCCCCCAGCACCACCCCUGCGCCUCUGCCUCCACACCCACACCCUCACCCCCACUCCGUGGCCCUACCUCCUGCCCACCUCCCCGUGCAGCAGCAGCAGCCACAGCAGAAGACCCCUCUGCCAGCCCCUCCUCCCCCACCGGCUGCCCCUGCCCAGACACUGGUGCCAGCUCCAGCCCAUCUGGUGGCGACGGCUGGGGGUGGCUCCACGGUCAUCGCCCACACAGCCACCACUCACGCUUCAGUCAUCCAGACUGUGAACCACGUUCUGCAGGGGCCAGGCGGCAAGCACAUCGCCCACAUCGCCCCCUCGGCCCCCAGCCCUGCGGUGCAACUGGCGCCUGCCACACCCCCCAUUGGGCACAUCACUGUGCACCCUGCCACCCUCAACCAUGUGGCCCACCUGGGCUCCCAGCUGCCCUUGUACCCGCAGCCCGUGGCAGUGAGCCACAUCGCCCACACCCUCUCGCACCAGCAAGUCAACGGCACGGCCGGCCUGGGGCCCCCGGCUACUGUCAUGGCAAAGCCGGCCGUGGGGGCUCAGGUGGUGCACCACCCCCAGCUGGUGGGCCAGACCGUGCUCAACCCUGUGACCAUGGUCACCAUGCCCUCCUUCCCAGUCAGCACACUCAAGCUGGCUUGAGGACGAGGCCACUCAGAGGCCCCCAGUGGGGACAGGGAGGGGGACCUGUCCCCCACUCUCUCACCCACCAGCUCCACACAUUCCAGCCAGGCCCAGGCCAGCCCCCCCACCCACCCCCAGGCCUCCUAGGGGAAGGGGGUGCAAAGACUCUGAGCCAAGGGAGGGAAGGGCCACCCUGCUGCACUAGGACUUGGUAAGAUGACUCUGAGAAAAUGCGAGACUCUGAUGGAAUGUGCCACCUGUCCGGCCCAGUGCCAGCUCCAGUGCCGCUCCUGCUUCCCCUCCCUACCCUCGGAAAUCAGUGCGAUGUGGACGUCACGCUCCCUGACUUCUCCCCCGCCCUGCCCCGCCUUCGUGUGCUGCUGCUGCUAUUGCUGUCUGGUGAGGUGGCCCAGGCCCCCGGCUUUCCUCCGGAGCCUCAUGUUCUCUUCCCAGGCCUUUGGAGGGGAAAUGGGGAAAGCAGAACUGAAGCCACUUGGCCCAGAAAGCUGCGGAUUGGGGUGAUAAGGGGCCUUGCUCUGAGCACAGGUGACAGAUCAUAGGAAGUGGCUGGUCUGGAGUCCCACCCGGACAGGUGGGGCCUCAGCCUGGGGCUCUCUGACCCGGUUGCAGUCACUGUGAUUCGUUACCGUAGAUACUACUUAAAAUGAUUCUCUACCAACAAUAAACCAAACCCAGCCACUGCCAAGCUUCCUGUGCCCUCACCCCAAUCCCUGCCACUGGGCUCUGGACCUCAGGAGGGCAGGCUGAGGUGGGGAAGGAGGGACUUGGCUGUCCUUCCCCUUCCCCGUCCCCUGCAGCCUGGGUCUGGAUGGGAGGAGAGCCACUGGGCCCCUGUCCCCAGUCCCCAGUCCCCAGCCCUGGGCUUGGCUCUUGGCUUCCAGAAGGCAGCAAAGAGGGGCGCUGUCCUGCGUUCAGCCCCUGAUCUCUGACCUCUGCUGAGUGCUGGGCACUGCUCCAAGGGACAGGUGGGCCUGGCGGCCUGUGGGUUUGGGUGCCUCCUGCAGUUUGGGAGACAUGGACCAGCAUCUGGUCUUGUUUCCAGGAGCAUAGAAGCCACAUCGUUGAGACAUCAGGAAGGUAAAAACCCAGCGGCUUAGCCAAGCCCUAAGCCUGUCCCCAGACCAACCCUGGGACCUAUACAGAACAGAGGGCCAGAGCUAGGGCUGCUGCUUCUGCUCCAGCCCCUUUGCCUCUGUCCUCCCAUCCCCUCAACACCCUGCUUCUCCCGGGGACGCUUUUGAGUGGGCCCUGCCCGGGGAGCUGCAGAGCAGCAGCACCUUUCUCUGAGAAGAGGUCCUUGGUUGGGUCAAGGACAGGGCUGAGCGUGGAAGGGGGAGGAGUCAGGGGCUCUGUGUUAGGAUGCGGCUUUCUCUGCCUCUGGGCAGCCUGCUUUGGCCUUUCCUUGUAUGUGGGUGUUUAUUACAAGUGGCUUUGUGUCAGACACGCUCGGCUCCCCACCUGGACACACACUCACCAGUGGCCUUUCAGUGUAGCGGGAGGAAGCCGGUGUCCCUGGAUGUGAAGCUCACACUGAUGGGCUGGGGCAGGGGCCUGGGCCGGCGAGGGGGCCGGGGGGAGGGGACAGAGCUGAGGAUUUCCUGGAGUGCCCUGCAGGCACAGAGGAGGUCAGCAAAGGUCUUGAAUAGAUUUUCUCUGGAAAUAAAGAAUCCUUAGAUGCCUAAAAAUUCCCUUCCUGUUCCCUCCUGGUCCUGGACACCUCCCAGGGGACUGUUCCUUAUUUCUCUCUCCUGGUGUGGGUAAAGGGACAGUUACAAACCAGGUCACCAUCCUCAGAGGCUGAGCCCUGUACCCACCCCAGCACAGCCACCUCCGCCAGACCCCGUGGCUCUGGGAGAGCCAGCUUUGCUAUUCCCAUUGUGACAGCGAUGGCAGGCCUGACCCACGGGGCAGUUAGAGCAGCCUCGUGGAGCUCGCCCCUCCCCUCAGCCUGCCCACCUCUCCCUGCAUCCUGAGGCCAGUGGCCCCCGGGCCUGCACAGAUACCUCAUCAUCCACCCGCUGCCCCUCCCCGUCCCUGUCCCCCAGCAUCGGGGGCCUGCAAAUCUAGUGCCGAAUGACUAUGUCCAGAUUGGUGACGAUGGGUGUUGCUGUUUUUCUUGUCGUUUGUGAACGCUGUGAUGCUGUGUGCCCAAGUGGGCAGUCACCACCCAGCCCUUCCUUGGGCGUCUCCCCCAGAGUGCUGUCGGGACCACAUCUGUCCUCACCCUGUGGGACCGCCUGGCCCUCCCUCCCUAGCCCUUCCAGCCUGGGACACACACACACACACACACACACACACACGCACGCACACGCACACAUCUUACCUCUCAUGCGUGUUUUACCUUUUGAUGUUCAGAGUGGCUCACUGGCUGGGAGUCCUUACCUCGGGGAGAGGGGGAGGUUGGUUCCUUGGGGGGCCAAAGAAGGCAGGGAAUGCCUGGAGGGUAACUGGGGGGCCACCAUGACCCCUUCUCUCUCCAGAAACAGCUGCUUCUCCCCCCAUCCCAGGGUCCCACCCCCAACCCCCAGAGGUGGCCCUUGUUUACAGUGAGGACUCGGCCACUGUGUCUCUGUUUCCUGAAAUAUAAACUGUAGCGACCCCAGACUGUAGAGAUUUUUAUGUGUUUGGAUACAUCUGCUGUGUGGAAAAAAAAAAAAACUACAAAAACCCUAAUUUUGUACAUACUGUAUUUUUACUAUUGAACUGUAUUCUAGUGGCUGUUCAUGCUCCAAGACUUUAGUUACCGAGACAUGAAUACUAUCCAUGUAAUAAGCACUUGCCUGGAAUAAAAUAUAAAACUGAAAUAAACCUGCACUGAAACCUGA